AGUCCAUAUAGAGCUGUCCUACAGCAUUCUGGAAACUUGAGGAUGUGCGGUGCAUAAAGGGGCUGGAAGUGACCCACCUGUGAUGAGCCCUUUCUAAGGAGAAGGGUUUCCAAGAGAUCACCCCACCAGAAAAGGGUAGGAAUGAGCAAGUUGGGAAUUUUAGACUGUCACUGCACAUGGACCUCUGGGAAGACGUCUGGCGAGAGCUAGGCCCACUGGCCCUACAGACGGAUCUUGCUGGCUCACCUGUCCCUGUGGAGGUUCCCCUGGGAAGGCAAGAUGCCCAACAACAGCACUGCUCUGUCAUUGGCCAAUGUUACCUACAUCACCAUGGAAAUUUUCAUUGGACUCUGCGCCAUAGUGGGCAACGUGCUGGUCAUCUGCGUGGUCAAGCUGAACCCCAGCCUGCAGACCACCACCUUCUAUUUCAUUGUCUCUCUAGCCCUGGCUGACAUUGCUGUUGGGGUGCUGGUCAUGCCUUUGGCCAUUGUUGUCAGCCUGGGCAUCACAAUCCACUUCUACAGCUGCCUUUUUAUGACUUGCCUACUGCUUAUCUUUACCCACGCCUCCAUCAUGUCCUUGCUGGCCAUCGCUGUGGACCGAUACUUGCGGGUCAAGCUUACCGUCAGCUCCAUCUCCCCUACCCUUUAGCAAUUACUGCUGUGGACUCACUGACUCUCUUCAUUCACACAGAUACAAGAGGGUCACCACUCACAGAAGAAUAUGGCUGGCCCUGGGCCUUUGCUGGCUGGUGUCAUUCCUGGUGGGAUUGACCCCCAUGUUUGGCUGGAACAUGAAACUGACCUCAGAGUACCACAGAAAUGUCACCUUCCUUUCAUGCCAAUUUGUUUCCGUCAUGAGAAUGGACUACAUGGUAUACUUCAGCUUCCUCACCUGGAUUUUCAUCCCCCUGGUUGUCAUGUGCGCCAUCUAUCUUGACAUCUUUUACAUCAUUCGGAACAAACUCAGUCUGAACUUAUCUAACUCCAAAGAGACAGGUGCAUUUUAUGGACGGGAGUUCAAGACGGCUAAGUCCUUGUUUCUGGUUCUUUUCUUGUUUGCUCUGUCAUGGCUGCCUUUAUCUAUCAUCAACUGCAUCAUCUACUUUAAUGGUGAGGUACCACAGCUUGUGCUGUACAUGGGCAUCCUGCUGUCCCAUGCCAACUCCAUGAUGAACCCUAUCGUCUAUGCCUAUAAAAUAAAGAAGUUCAAGGAAACCUACCUUUUGAUCCUCAAAGCUUGUGUGGUCUGCCAUCCCUCUGAUUCUUUGGACACAAGCAUUGAGAAGAAUUCUGAGUAGUUAUCCAUCAGAGAUGACUCUGUCUCAUUGACCUUCAGAUUCCCCAUCAACAAACACUUGAGGGCCUGUAUGCCUGGGCCAAGGGAUUUUUACAUCCUUGAUUACUUCCACUGAGGUGGGAGCAUCUCCAGUGCUCCCCAAUUAUAUCUCCCCCACUCCACUACUCUCUUCCUCCACUUCAUUUUUCCCUUGUCCUUUCUCUCUAAUUCAGUGUUUUGGAGGCCUGACUUGGGGACAACGUAUUAUUGAUAUUAUUGUCUGUUUUCCUUCUUCCCAAUAGAAGAAUAAGUCAUGGAGCCUGAAGGGUGCCUAGUUGACUUACUGACAAAAGGCUCCAGUUGGGCUGAACAUGUGUGUGGUGGUGACUCAUUUCCAUACCAUUGUGGAAUUGAGCAGAGAACCUGCUCUCGGAGGAUGCCUAGGAGAUGUUGGGAACAGAAAAAAUAAACUGAGUUUAAGGGGGACUUAAACUGCUGAAUUCACCUGUGGAUGUUUUUGAGUAAAUAAAAGCUAAUAGCUAA